UCCACCAUGGAUGUGGCCUUGAAGUUAGGGGCAGGCUUUCCCAUGCACGCAUUACCUGAGGCCAUGACUGAACAAGCUGUGUGGGCAAAGGCUAGAUGCACGGACGAUCACGUGCGUGGACCCGCGUUCUCAGUGCCCAUGUGACUAAUUAAAAUUUUUUUUUUUUUUUUUUUAGAAUUGGCAUCUUGCUAUGUUGCCCAGGCUGGUCUUGAACUUCUAGCCUCAAGUGAUACUCCUGCCUUGGCCUCCCAAAGUGUUGGGAUUACUGGCAUGACCCAAUGUGCCUGGCCCAGGGCAAUUCUUAAAAUAACAACAAAGUUUGGUGGACGUAUUGACUCUUCCUUUUGUGAAAAAUUUCUCCAUAGCAUGCAAUUAUACUGUUUGAUAGCAUUUUACCCACAGUAGCAAUUCUUUCACAAUUGGAGUCAAUCCUCUCCAAACCCUGCUGCUGCUUUAUCAACUAGGAUUAUGUAGUAAUCUAAAUCCUUUAUUGUUAUUUCAACAGUGUUCACAAGCAUCUUCACCAGGAGUAGAUUGCAGCUCAAGAAGCCACUUUCUUUGCUCAUGCAUAAGAAACAACUCAUCCAUUCAAGUUUUUUUUUUAAUUUUUUGUAGAGAUGGGGUCUUGCUGUGUUGCCCAGGCUGGUCUUGAACUCCUGGUCUUAAGUGAUCCUUUUGCCUUGGCCUCCCGAAAUGUUGAGAUUACGGGUGUGAGCCACUGUGCCCUACCCCGUUUAUGUUUUGUCAUGAGAUUGCAGCAAUUCAGUCACAUCUACAAGCUCCACUUCUAAUGCUAGUUCUCUUGCUUUUUCUACCACAUCUGCAGUGAUUUCCUCCAAUAAAGUCUUGAAACCCUCAGAGUCAUCCAUGAGGACUGGAAUCAAUUUCUGUAACACUCCUGUUAGUGUUAAUGUUUUGACAUCCUCCCUUGAAUCACAAAUGUUCUUACUGGCAUCUAGAAGGGUGACUCUGUUCCAGAAAGUGUUCAAUUUACUUUGCCCAGUUUCAUCAAAGGAAAUCACUAUCUAUGGCACCUAUAGCCUUAAAAAAUGUAUUUCUUAAAUAAUAAGAUUUGAAAGUUGAAAUAACUCCUUUAUCCAUGGCCUGCAGAAUGGAUAAGCAGGCAUGAAAACAGCAUUUAUCUCUUUGUACAUCUACAUCAGAGCUCUUUGGUGACCAGGUGCAUUGUCAGUGAGUGGCAAUAUUUUUAAAGGAAUCUUUUUUUCUGAGCCAUAGCUCUCAAAGUUGGGCUUAAAAUAUUCAGUAAGCCAUACUGUAAACAGAUGUGCUGUCAUCUAGACUUUGCUAUUCCAUUUACAGAGCACAGGCAGAGUAGCUUCAGCAUAACUCUUAAGGGCCCUAGGAUCUUCAUAUUAGUAAAUGAGCAUUGGCUUCAACUUCAAGUCGUCAGCUAAAUCAGCCCCUGACACGAGAGCCAGCCUGUCCUUUAAGGCUUUGAACCCAGGCAUUCACUUUUCCUCUCUAGCCAGGAAAGUCUUAGAUGAAAUAUUUUUCCAAUAGAAGGCUAUUUUGUCUACAUUGAAAAUCUGUUGUUUAGUGUAGCCACCUUCAUCAAUGAUCUUAGCUAGUUCUAGACAACUUGCUGCAGCUUCUACAUUAGCACUUGCUGCUUCACCUUGCACUUUUGUGUUAUGGAAAAGGCUUCUUUCCUUAAACCUCAUAAACCAGUCUCUACUUGCUUCAUACUUCUGCAGCAUCCUCACCUCUUUCAGCCUUCAUAGAAUUGAAGACAAUUAGGGUCUUGUUCUGGAUUAGGCUUUGGCUUAAGGGAAUAUUGUGGCUGGUUUAAUCUUCUGUCCAGACCACUCACACUUUCUCCAUAUCAGCAAUAAGGCUGUUUUGCUUUCUCAUCAUUCAUAUGUUCACUGGAGUAGCACUUUUAAUUUCUUUCAAGAACUUCUUCUUUGCAUUUACAACUUGGCUCUUUGGCACGAGAGAUCUACCUCUUGCCCUAUCUUAGCUUUCAACAUGCCUUGCUUGCUAAGCUUAGUCAUUUCUGGCCCUUGAUUUCAAGUGAGAGACAUGCAACUAUUCCCUUUCACUUGAACACUUAGAGGCUAUUGUAGGGUUCUUCAUUGGCCUAAUUUCAGUAUUGUGUCUCCGGGAAAAGGAGGCCCGAGGAGAAGAGAGAGAGAGGGCAACAGCCUAUUGGUAGGGCAGUCAGAACACAGUAUUUAUCAAUUAUAUUCACCUUGCUAUAGGGCAUGGUUUGUGGUGCCCCAAUACAAUUACAACAGUAACAUCACUGAUCACUAUUAACAGAUAUAAUAAAAAUGGAGAAGUUUGGAAUAUUGUGAGAAUUACCAAAAUGUGACAUAGAGACACAAAGUGAGCACAUGCUGUUAGAAAAAUGGCACCGGUAGACUUGCUGGAUGCACAGUUGCCAUGAAUCUUCAAAUUGUAAAAAAUGGUGUCUGCGAAGUGCAGUAAAAUGAGGCGCGGUAAACUGAGGUGGGCCUGUGUAGGGAGAAGGGAACAGGAGAGUGCAUGGUGAGAGUUGGAGGUCAAAUACAAAGUGGCAAAAGGGAGUUUUCUGGGGUGAUGGAAAUGUUCUUUACCUUUGUUGUGGUGGUAGUGGUGGUUAUGCAGUUUAUAAAGUUUUCAAAACUCAUCAACUGUACACUUAAAAUUAGUGGAAUUAAUUGUAUGAAAAUUAUACCUCAAUAAAGCUGAUUUUUAAAAAGCAGGCAGAAUUCAUCUGUGGUAUCAGAAUAGUGAUUAAAGUACUGACUGGGAGGGAUGAAGGAUCCUUCUGGGGAGUUGGAAGUGUUCUGUAUUUUGAAGGGGUGUUGCCGGGGUGUACACAGUGUAUGUGCACAGUGUAAAAGGUCAUUGAGCUGCACACUUAAGACUUGUGCACUUUAAGUUAUAUACCUCAAUAAAAAAGGAAAAAGUUCUAAAGAAGGAUUAUAAUAUAAAGUUGAGAACAUCUCCAAGAAAGUAGAGCAAAAGGACAGAGAGGUGGAAAAAAGGAGGGAAAAACUAAGAAAAUUAGAGGACCAGCUGAGGAAGUCUAAUUCCUGGAUAAAAGGCAUUUCACAGCAGAAAAAAAAUGGAAAGAAAUUUUUAAUGAAAUUCAGGAAAGAAAUUUUAAUAAUUCAGAAUAUUUCCUAAAAUGGAAAGACAUUAAUUUCUACAUUGAAAGAACCCCAGAUAGACCCAUUUCAAAGCAUAUCAUCAAAAAUUUUAGAAAACUCAUGUCAAAGAGAAGUUUCCAGAAAAGGGGAAAAACAAGUGAUAUAUAACGAAUUAGGAAUUUAAAUGACUUCAGUCUUCUUAACCUAAUAUUGAAACCUAAAAUGUAUUAGGGAAAUGCCAUAAAAAUUCUCAAGGAAAAUUAUUUCCAAACUAAGAUUCAGUAGCCAGGCAAAUUCUCAUGGAAGUAUGAGGGUAGAAUAAAGGUAUUUACAGACAUGCACAGUUGCAAAAAUUUUUUCUCCCAACUGUAGAAAAUGUGCUCCAUAAAGGUAAGAGAGUGAAAAAAGAAAGAGAAAGACAUGUGAUACAUAAAAAAAGGACAGCAUAGAGGAGGCAGAAGGGCUCCCCAGGAUGAAGGGAGGUACCAAGUUGAACAGCCUUGGAGGGUAGAAAGAGAUAGUGUCUUUCUCCAGAGCAAAGGUCAGGUUUGCUUACAGCCUUGGAAGAUACAGUAUCUCCCUUUGGAACAAGGGGUAGGGAAGCAUAAAACUUAAUAGAUUCAGGUUCUCUAAGCUUAGGCCUCCUCUCCUGUAAUGCAGACUACUUCCUUUGCAGGUGUUACAUGGCCCUUUUCAAAUUGCCCCAUGGGAAUUGGGGCUUGGGGAACUGAUGGAAAAAAAAAAAAUACCUUGGGUUAGGUUGUCUUCUGGAAGCUUUAUAGUUUUAACUCUUACAUUUAGGUCAGUAAUCCAUUUGAGUUAAUUUUUGUAUGUGAUGUGAAGUAAGGGUUGAGAUUCAGUUUUUGUUUUGCAUAUGGAUAGCCACUUUGUUUCAGGACCCUUUUGCUGGAAAAAAUUGUCCUUCCCUCAUUGAAUUGCUCUGGCACUUUGGUUGAAAAUUAGUUGGCUUUGUAUGUAUGAAUCUGUUUCUUGACUCUCUAGUUUCUUUCACUGAUCUUUGUGUCUGCCUUUAUGUCAGUUCCACACUGUCUUGAUUACCGUAACUUUAUUUUUUUUUGAGAUGGAGUUUCGCUCUUGUUGCCUUGGCUGGAGUGCAGUGGCGCGAUCUCGGCUCACUGCAACCUCCUCCUUCCAGGUCAAAGCAGUUCUCCUGCCUCAGCCUCCCGAGUAGCUGGGAUUACAGGCAUGCCCCACCGCACCCGGCUAGUUUUAUAUUUUUAGUAGAGACGAGGUUUCUUCAUGUUGGUCAGGCUGGUCUUGAACUCUCAACCUUAGGUGAUCCACUCUCCUCGGCUUCCCAAAGUGCUGGGAUUACAGGCAUGAGUCACCGUGCCCGGCCAUGAUUACUGUAACUUUAUAGUAAAUUUUAAAAUCAUGUAGUAGACAUCCACCCCCAACAGGCAUUUUUCCCCUCAACCCCUUAGAAGUACCCCACCUGAAUACAUCUGUGUUAGUAAGUCCUACUUUAUUGUUUUUCAGAACUUUUGUCUAUUUUGUGUUCUUUCAUUUCCAUGUAAGUUUUAGAAUCAGCUUGUCAAUUUUUCCUAAAAAGGCUGCUGGGAUUUUGAUUGGGAUUCCAUUGACUCUAUGGGUCACUUUCAAGAUAAUUUGACAUCUUACGCAUAUUGAGUGUUUUUAUUCAUAAACACAUACACACAUAUCUAUUAAUUUAGGUCAUCUUUAAUUCUCUUAGAUUUUAAUAGUUCUCAGGUUACAGAUCUUGCACAUAUUUUGUUAAAUUUAUCCCUGAAUAUUUAAUAUUUUUUGGAUGAUUUUACUCUUUUUAGUUUCCAGUUAUUUCUUGUAUGUGGAAAUAAGAUUGAUUUUUGUACACUGACCUCUUAUGCUGCAACCUUACACAACUCGUUUAUUAGUUCUGGAGCUAUUUGCAGAUUCCCUAGGAUUUUCUCCACUGACAAUCAUGUUUUCUGUAAAUAAAAGCAGCUUUACUUCUUUUCCAAUCUGCAUGCCUUUUAUUUUUGUAUCGCCUUAUUGCACUGGUUAGAACCUCAGUUCUAAUGUGGAAUAGAAGGGGUGAGAGCAAAUAUCCUUGUCUUGUUCUUGAUCUUGGAGAGCAUUUAGUCUUUCACAAUACAUAUGCUAGCCGUAGGUAUUUCAUAGAUGUCCAUUACUCGGUUGAGUAAAUUGCCUUUUAUUCUUAGUUUGCUAAGCAUUCUUAUGAAUUAUGUUGAAUUUUGUCAAAUACAUUUUCUGUAUCUAUUGAGAUGAUUUAUAAUGUUUCAUUUUUAUUCUCUUAAAAUUGUAUUGAUUGGUUUUAAAAUAAACCAUCUUGAAUUCUUGGGGAAAACGUCACUGGGUCAUAAUACAUUAUCUAUUUCGUCACUGGGUCAUAAUACAUUAUCUAUUUUACAUAUUGCUGGAUUUGAUUAGCUAAAAUUUAAAGAUUUUUUGUAUCUAUGUUUUUAAGGGAUAUUGAUAUUGUAAUUUUCUGAUAAGAUCUUUGUCUGAUUUUGGUGUAAGGCUAACACUGGCUUUAAAAUAUGAGUUGGAUAGCCAAAAGAACUAUGGCAAAAAAAGGAAAAAAAAAGAGUUGGAAAUAUUUCUACCUCUUCUGUAUUCAAUUUCAUUAAUUGAUAAAGGAGUAUUCCGAUUAACUACUCUGUCUCUUCUUGGGCAAGCUUUGGUGUGUGACCAUCAUAGAAUUUGUCCAUUUCAUUAAACUCUCUUUUGUCUUUCAGUAGCUCCAAGGUUUGUAGUGAUAGCCCUCCUUCAUUUUUUGUUUUGGUAAUGUGUAUUUUUUUUUUUCUCUCUUUCCUGGUCAAUCCUACUAGAGGUUUAUUCAUUUUAUUGAUAUUUGUGAAGAACCUGCUUUUGGCUACAUUGAAAUUUUCUCUUGUUUUUCUGUUUUCUAUUUCAUUGAUUUCUUCCCUCAACUUUAUUACAUUGUUCCUUCUGCUUCUUUUGGUUUUAAUUUGCUUCCCUUGCUAGAUUCUUAAGAUAGAAGCUGAAAGCAAGAGUCGGCAAACUGCAGUCCAGGGGCCAAAUCCAGCUUGCCACUUGUUCUUGAAUGGCUCAUGAAUCAGGAAUGAUUUUUGCAUUUUUAUAAGGUUGAAGAAAAAUCAAAAGAAGAAUACUAUUUUGUGACAUGUGGAAAUUAAAUGAAAUUCAGAUUUCAUUGUCCACAUAUAAGGUUUUAUUGGAACACAACCACACUUAGUUGUUUACAAAUUGUCUCUGGCUGCUUUUGUGCUGGAAUGGCAAAGUUGAGGGGUUGUGACAGAAACCAUGUGGCAUUCUCAUUGCUUUUGCACUGCUGUUUCUGAACUGUAAUCACUGUUUUAAGUGCCAUGCAUAUCACUGUGCUGUGACAUUUUACUUUAUUAUCAAUGCAUACACAUCAUGUCAAAACAAGAAAAGAUGAAAAAAAUAGACUUGGAAUGUUAUACUUUUAAAGCAUGCUGAAGCAUGGAUUAUUGAGUUAUGACAAGGCAUUGUAUUAUGCAGUGAUACUAUAGCUGUGUUAAAUACAAUAUACACUGAUAUUACCAGACUCUGCAUUCAUCACAAUAUUCCCAACUCACAGGAAAGUAAUGGUCAGAAAAAUGAGAAAACAUAAAAAGGAAUAUCUUAUUCCAGUAGAAUUUCUUUACAAAAUUAGAAAAUAAAAAUCAGGCUGCACCCAGAGUAAACUUCCAAGUGGCUCAUUUGUUAACCAAGCAAGGAAGUCAUUUAUCAAUAGUGAAGUAACUAAAUUGUGUUGGUUACAACAGGCGCAGAAUUGUGUCUGGAGAAGGUAAACUUAAGACUGUUAGUCUUUUGGCAAGAAGAGUUGCUCAAAGAAUUGAGGACAUCAAUAAUCAAUUAAAAAGGCAAAUUAUUUUGAGUGGUUUUCCUUGGCUUUUGAUGAGUUGACAGAUGUUACCAAUACUGCUCAGUUGUUUAUUUGAAAAGUCAAGGCUGAGUUUGAAGUGUUAAAUAAUCUUAAUGAAUAGUGUGUGUAGAAUAGCUAAAGAUAAGAAUAUUUCAAAAAGUUGAGAAAACACUAAUGGCAUGCAACCUGAAUGAAGUGUAGUCUGCUAAGAUGUGUUAUAACUGAUGGUAGUAAAAAUUUGUAUAGAAUAGAAAAGAAUUCAGGUGGACAAAUAAAGCUGUGAAAGUGUAAGAAGUUUGAAGUCUACAGUUACUUAUUUUAUUUCUUAGCAGGUAUUUUGCAGAGAAUGUUUGAAUCUAUCAUGUAAUCUUGAACCAGUAGUGUCAACAUUUGCUCUUGUGGACUUAACCAUUGUCAGUUCUAGGAAUUUUUGUCAGAAAUAGAAGCUGAAUAUUCUCACUUGCCCUGCUGUACAGCAAUUUGAUGGUUUAAUAGUUGUAAGGCUUUAUUGCAAACUUUUGAAUUUAGAAGUGAGAUUGAAAUUUUUCUGAAUGUGAGAAACUGCUGUCAAUCUGAAUAUUGAACGCUGAAUGGCUUUAGAAAUCAAUUUGUGAUGCAGACUCAAUAGUAUUUCUUAAUGAAUUCAACCUAAAAUUACAAGACAAAACAGUUGUUAUAUCAAAACUAAUACUGCAGUAAAGUUAUUUCAAUGGCAACCACUAUUCUUUGAAUCACAAGUAAUAUCAAGUAAUUUUAUAUAGCUUUCCAUGCUGUUAUAAGUUAAAGCAAAGAAGUAAGGUCUCCAUUCCUACCCAGUUUGCAAUAGGUAUGUUUUCUGAGUUCAAACUACAGUUUCAGCAGCAUUUUUUAGAACUCGAUGUAAGUGCCAAGGAAAUUUCCAUUUAACUGUGCAGUUGAGGCACUUCUUAUUUAACCUUUAAUUGGAAUGAUUAAUCUGCAAAUAAUGGCACGUAAAUACUAAGAGUAAAUCCUUUAGAUGCCUUCCAAACAAUGAUUAUGCUGAAUUGAAAUCAUAUGCUUGUGACUACUAUCAGUAUAAAGUAGCACCUAACCUACUUUGAAAAGUAGACAUUUUCAAACAUGAAAUGUAUUGUAUUCAAGGUAAACAUUAGAAUGUAUGAACAUUUGUGAUUGAUUUUGAUGAUAGGGAAUACUAACUUUGAAUCCCAACUAAGUGAAAUAUUGUCCCUAAAAAGAGUUUCAUUCUUCUCCUUAGUCAACCUGUCUUACAGAAAGUUGUACUCUGUUAUUGUUUCUAUAAUAUUUUGAAUUGCAUCGAUAAGAAUUAUGGAAUUUUUUGUCUCAUUAUAUAAGUAGUUAUAUAAUAUCCUUCAUUUUGUUUGUUAGCUGUCAAAGCCUAAAAUAUUUACUUGUUAGGUCUUUUACAGGAAAAGUUUGGCAACCCCUGAUUUGUAUCAGGAUAUUUUUAUCUUUUAUAGUUUUGUGUCUGUAUUUGUAAGUAGGAUUUAUGCUUUUGUUUCACAAUGACUUUAAAGGGAAAUAAUUUAUAGAGCAUCUUUGUUUCUACUGGAUUUAUUAAUUACAUAUUAUUCAUUAUAAUAAGGCCAUAUUGUUUCGUGUUAAUGUUCUAAAUUUGAAGAUGACACUUUGUGUGGUUGUCCUGUAUUCUGUGGAUAGAUCCACUGGACAUUGAAAUUUGUUACUGUGUAAAAGUAGUUGUAUUAGUCCAUUCUCAUGCUGCUAUGAAGAAAUACCUGAGACUGGGUAAUUUAUAAAGAAAAGAGGUUUAAGUGACUCACAGUUCUGCAUGGUUGGGGAGGCCGCAGGAAACUUACAAUCAUGGCGGAAGGCACCUCUUCACAGGGCUGCAGGAGAGAGAAUGAAUGCCAGCAGGGGAAAUGGCAGAUGCUUAUAAACCCAUCAGAUCUCAUGAGACUCACACAUUAUCAUGAGAACAGCAUGGGGGAACCACCCCCAUGAUCCAGUCACCUCCAUGUGCUCCUGCCCUUGACAUGUGAUUAUUACAAUUCAAGGUGAGAUUUGGGUGGGAACACAGAGCCAAACCAUAUCAUCCUGCCUGUGGCCCUUCCCAAAUCUUAUGUCCUCACAUUGCAAAUCAUUCCUUUCCAACCGUCCCCCAAAGUCUUAACCCAUUCCAGACUCAAAAGUCCAAAUCCAAAGUCUCAUCUGAGACAAGGCAAGUUCCUUCCACCUAUGAGCCUGCUUCAAAAGCAAGUUAGUUACUUUCUAGAUAUAAGGGGAGUAUAAGCAUUGGGUAAAUAUACCUGUUCCAAAUGGGAGAAAUUGGCUAAAACAAAGGGAUAUAGGCCAUGCAGUUCUGAAAUCCAAUCGGGCAGUCAUUAAACCUUAAACUUCCAAAAUUAUCUCCUUUGACUCCACGUCUGACAUCCAGGUCACACUGAUGUCAGAGGUAGGUUCCCAUGGCCUUGGGCAGCUCCACCCCUGUGGCUUUGCAGGGUACAUCCCCACCUUCUGGCUGCUUUCACAGCUGACCUUGAGUGUCUGUGGCUUUUCCAGAUGCAUAAUGCAAGCUGUCAGUGGAUCUACCAUUCCGGGAUCUGUAGGAUGGUGGCCCUCUUCUUACAGCUCCACUAGGCAGUGCCCUAGUGGGGACUCAGUGGAAGUUCCAGCCACACAUUUCCCUUCCACACUUCCCUAGCAGAGGUUCUCCAUGAGGGUCCUGCCCCUGCAGCAGACUUCUGCCUGGACCUCCAGGCAUUUCCAUACAUCCUCUGAAAUCUAGGUGGAGGUUCCCAAACCUCAGUUCUCAUCCUGUGCACUUGCAGGCCCAGCACCAUGUGGAAGCUGCCAAAACUUGGGGCUUGUACCCUCUGAAGCCAUGGCCUGAGUUGUACCUUGGCCCCUUUUAGCCAUGGCUGGAGUGGCUGGGUGCAGAGCACCAAGUCCCGAGGCUGCACACAGCAGAGGGGCCCUGGACCCAGCCCAGGAAACCCAUUUUUCCCUCUUAGGCCUCUGGGCUUGUGAUGGGAGGGGUUGCCGACAUCUCUGACAUGCCCUGGAGGCAUUUUCCCCAUUGUCUUGGUGAUUAGCUUUUGAUUCCUUGUUACUUAUGCAAAUUUCUGCAGCUGGCUUGAAUUUCUCCCCAGAAAAUGGGUUUUUCUUUUCUAUUGCAUUGUCAGGCUACACAUUUUCUAAACCUCUAUUCACUGCUUCCCUUUUAAACAUAAAUUCCAAUUCCAAACCAUAUCUUUGUGAAUGCUUAAAACUGUAUGCUUUUAAGAGCAAUCCCCCCUUCCAAAUCACCUCUUGAACACUUUGCUGCUUAGAAAUUUAUUCUGCCAGAUACCAUAAACACCUCUCUCAAGUUCAAAGUUCCACAAAUCUCUAGGGCAGGGACAAAAUGCUGCCAGUCUCUUUGCCAAAGCACAGCAAGGACAAGUUCUUCUUCAUCUGCAACCACCUCAGCUUGAACUUCAUUGUCCAUAUCACUAUCAUCAUUUUGGUCAAAACCAUUCAGCAAGUCUCUAGGAAGUUCCAGAGUUUCCCACAUUUUUCUGUGUUCUUCUGAGCCCUCCAAACUGUUCCAACCUCUGCCUGCUACCCAGUUCCAAAGUCACUUCCACAUUUUCAGGUAUCCUUGUAGCAGCACACCACUCCUGGUACUAGUCUACUGUAUUAGUCCUUUCUCACACUGCUGUGAAGAAAAACUUGAGACUGGGUAAUUUAUAAAGAAAAGAGGUUUAAUUGACUCCCAGUUCUGCAUGGCUGGGGAGGCUCAGAAAACUUAGAAUCAUGGGGGAAGGCACCUCUUCACAGGGCAGCAGGAGAGAGAAUGCAUGCCAGCAGGGGGAAUACCAGAUGCUUAUAAAACCAUCAGAUCUCAUGAGACUUACUCAUUAUCACAAGAACAGCAUGGAGGAAACUGUCCCCUUGAUCCGUUACCACCACGUGGUCCUGCCCUUGACACGUGGUGAUUAUUACAAUUUAAGGUGAGAUUUGGGUGGGGACACAGAGCCAACCCGUAUUAGUAGUGUACUAUUUGUUGCAGUGUGAUUCUCAAGUAAUACAACUCUGCCUUCAUGGAACCUUAUAAGAGGAAAAUAACAUGCCAAACACAUAAACAUUUGUUUUUAAAAAUGUGUUGGAGUCCUUUGAAAUGCCUAGAACUAGUGAUGGUUAAUUUUCAGGAAGAAUUUUUGAGUCCCUGAAGAACAGAUAAGAGAUUGAGAGUCAGAGUAGAAGAGUCAGGCUCCCCAAACCAAAGUUUAAUUCCCUGAAGAAGGCAUAGAGUAGUAUUUUGAUUUUCUUCUUUAUGUGUAUUCAUUGGUUUACUGUUCCUGGAAAUCAGAAGGCAAUUUUGACACUUUCUCAGGAUAUCAUUCUCCUGUAACUCUGGACUUGCUAUUCUUUUUAGUCUUGGGAGGAAAGUAUCUUUGCAUAGAAGCCUUGGAUGAUUCUAGGAGACUUUUGGAAAGCCUGGAAGAAAAGCCAGAAUUACUGGACUGGAGAGCUUUGGUGGAAGCCAGAAAUCUAGAGGGUAUUCUAACUAACAUCUUAUAGAAAGGAAAAUAACAAUAGUUAUUUGCAUGGCCAAAAAGAUAUAGAGAAUGAUGGGGUCUUAGAAGAUUACAAAUUGGGGUUCAGAGAGUGUAAUUUAUAGGUGUUUGCUUAGAUUUAAGUUUGAGGCAAUUACAUGAGUAUAAAUGGUACAUGGACAACUAUAGACUGUUCUUUAAAAUGUAUUCUUUAAGUAUAACUUUUUAUUCUUGGGGCCAAGAAGUUUUAGUGAUAACUAGUUUUUAUAGUUUCAACUGACUUCAGUAGAAAAUAUAUUCAUAUAUUUAUGUGAUAUUCAUAUUUUUUAUAUUGUCAAGAAUAAAUUGAAUAAAAAAAAAUUUCAUCUGUUAUUGCAGCCUAUGGUAAUUAUAAAGGAAUAAGGAAAACUAGUGUCCGGUUUUAUGUACCUGUAAGUAAAUCAGUAGUUCAGAGCUGUGUAACCUUUCUCCCUAUUAUUUCCGUGGGUGUUCUUUUGUAAUCUCCUUUGUACUUCCAAAUUUGAAAACGUUGUUUAGUGUUGUAAGAUGCAUUCAGAUAACCUCAAAGAAUGGUAACUAUUUUGACUUUCAAAGUAGUUCUAGACUGGGCGCAGUGGCUCACGCCUGUAAUCCCAGCACUUUGGGAGGCUUAGGUGGGUGGAUCACCUAAGGACAGGAGUUCAAGACCAGCCUGGCCAACACAGUGAAACCCAUCUCUACUAAAAAUACAAAAAUUAGCCGGGCAUGGUGGUGCACCCCUAUAGUUGCAGCUACUCAGGAAUCACUUGAACCUGGGAGGUGGAGGUUGCAGUGAGUCAAGAUCAUGCUGCUGCACUCCAAUCUGGGCAAUAAAGUCUCUGAAAGAAGAUGAAUUUGGCUGAGAUUUGUGAUAAUGCAAAGAAAGGAAGAGAAUAUGCCCUUCUUGGAAAUUACGACUCAUCAAUGGUAUAUUACCAGGGGGUGAUGCAGCAGAUUCAGAGACAUUGCCAGUCAGUCAGAGAUCCAGCUAUCAAAGGCAAAUGGCAACAGGUUCGGCAGGAAUUAUUGGAGGAAUAUGAACAAGUUAAAAGUAUUGUCAGCACUUUAGAAAGUUUUAAAAUUGACAAGCCUCCAGAUUUCCCUGUGUCCUGUCAAGAUGAACCAUUUAGAGAUCCUGCUGUUUGGCCACCCCCUGUUCCUGCAGAACACAGAGCUCCACCUCAGAUCAGGCGUCCCAAUCGAGAAGUAAGACCUCUGAGGAAAGAAAUGGCAGGAGUAGGAGCCCGGGGACCUGUAGGCCGAGCACAUCCUAUAUCAAAGAGUGAAAAGCCUUCUACAAGUAGGGACAAGGACUAUAGAGCAAGAGGGAGAGAUGACAAGGGAAGGAAGAAUAUGCAAGAUGGUGCAAGUGAUGGUGAAAUGCCAAAAUUUGAUGGUGCUGGUUAUGAUAAGGAUCUGGUGGAAGCCCUUGAAAGAGACAUUGUAUCCAGGAAUCCUAGCAUUCAUUGGGAUGACAUAGCAGAUCUGGAAGAAGCUAAGAAGUUGCUAAGGGAAGCUGUUGUUCUUCCAAUGUGGAUGCCUGACUUUUUCAAAGGGAUUAGAAGGCCAUGGAAGGGUGUACUGAUGGUUGGACCCCCAGGCACUGGUAAAACUAUGCUAGCUAAAGCUGUUGCCACUGAAUGUGGUACAACAUUCUUCAACGUUUCGUCUUCUACACUGACAUCUAAAUACAGAGGUGAAUCUGAGAAGUUAGUUCGUCUGUUGUUUGAGAUGGCUAGAUUUUAUGCCCCUACCACGAUCUUCAUUGAUGAGAUAGAUUCUAUCUGCAGUCGAAGAGGAACCUCUGAUGAACAUGAGGCAAGUCGCAGGGUCAAGUCUGAACUGCUCAUUCAGAUGGAUGGAGUUGGAGGAGCUUUAGAAAAUGAUGAUCCUUCCAAAAUGGUUAUGGUAUUGGCUGCUACUAAUUUCCCGUGGGACAUUGAUGAAGCUUUGCGAAGAAGGUUAGAAAAAAGGAUAUAUAUACCUCUCCCAACAGCAAAAGGAAGAGCUGAGCUUCUGAAGAUCAACCUUCGUGAGGUCGAAUUAGAUCCUGAUAUUCAACUGGAAGAUAUAGCCGAGAAGAUUGAGGGCUAUUCUGGUGCUGACAUCACUAAUGUUUGCAGGGAUGCCUCUUUAAUGGCAAUGAGACGGCGUAUCAAUGGCUUAAGUCCAGAAGAAAUCCGUGCACUUUCUAAAGAGGAACUUCAGAUGCCUGUUACCAAAGGAGACUUUGAAUUGGCCCUAAAGAAAAUUGCUAAGUCUGUCUCUGCUGCAGACUUGGAGAAGUAUGAAAAAUGGAUGGUUGAAUUUGGAUCUGCUUGAAUUUCUGUCAGCUCUUUAAUUUCUGGUAUUUUUGUUGAUAAAAUACGAAGAAAUUCCUGCAAUUUUUAAAAAACAAGUUUGGAAUUUUUUUCAGUGGAGUGGUUUUCGCUUAAAGGAAAAAAAAAUCUAAAACUGCGAAGAAUACUAAAUGUAGUUGAGAAAUAAUUGAUGGCGAGAGUUUGCUAGUCUCCCUCCCCGGCUUUGUGCUGGUAUUCCACGUAUUCCUGCAUUAAUAUUGCACACCCAAACCAGUCUAUCAGGGAGGCUGAAGCAAGGGCGCAGUGUGAUAUUUUAGGAAUACAGAAGAUUUAGAAAUACCCCUAUUUCUCAUUUGCAGUUUUUUUUUCCAAUUCUGUGCUCUGUCAACAUGAGGGACCUAUCUAUGUAUGUUGACUUUUAACAUCAAAAUUGGAUUUGUGUCAAACAUUCAUUGUUAAGAGAAGAAUGACAGUAUAUUUUGGAGGAAAUAAUGAAUUUACUAAUUAAACCUUUAGAAUUUAUGACUUACUGUUAGAGUCUGUCAUAUGGUUAGAAUUUUUACUUCCGCUACCCCUGCCAUUUCUUCUGCUAGCUACUUCAUAAUAUCUUGAGCUUUACUGAGGAAUAUUCUCACGCUCUGUGGUAUUUGAAUCAUUUUGCCAGGUCAUUUCUCUGUCUUUAGUAUUUUUUGCUGGUGCUUCUUACAUUUAAUAUGGAAAGGUGGGAAGAAUAUUACUGCAUUAGAUGUAAUUCUUCAUUCUAGACUUCCAAGUUUGUUUUCACUUUUUUGUGUGUGCGUGAAGGAGUCUGUGUCACCCAGGCUGUGUAGUGCAGUGGUUGAUCUUGGCUCACUGCAACCUCUGCCUCCUAGAUUCAAGCAAUUCUCCUGUCUCAGCCUCCCAAGUAGCUGGGAUUACAGGUGCGCACCACCAUGCCUGGCUGUGUUUUCACUUUUCUUUCAACAUGUUCAACCAGAUAUAUAGCCAUUAUUUUUCUCAGCUCCAGCAUUGUUUGAUUUUUCUUGAGUUUGAUUUUAGUAUUUGAGAUAAAUACUUUUACAUUCUAAACAAGUCCACUCUCUGUGGCUAACGCAAAACAAAUGAAAUCUUUAUUGUUUUCCAAACAGCUAGUUUAACAAAACAGCAUCAUACAUAGUGAAUGAUGUUCAUUGGAAAAUUCUAAAAUUUGUCCUUGUCUAGGUUGAGAACUUUUACACACACUAAGAUAAAGAUAGAAAUCUGACAUGCUCACUCAAUUCAGCAGGAAUUACACAUUAGAAAGAAGCCAGAAAAAUAAAUGGCAUAUAUCCAAUCACAAGUAAAUGAUCCUGGCGUUAGUUUUUAUGAUUACAUGUGUCUCAUUAGGCAAUUUAUGCUUUAAUGGUCAAGCUUUUAAAAAUUUGUAUUUGAUAACAUCCUGAAUUCUCAGUUUCGAAUAGUGCCUACUGGUUUAAAACUAAAAAUAAUACAGCUUUUUGGACAUUUAACCAAGAUACUAAGAAGGUUUUUUUUAAAAAAAGAGAUUUGAUUAUUUUUCCCUGCUAAAAACUGUAAAUGCCUUAUGUUCUUUUCAGAUAACUUAAGUCUGACCUAAACUCCAGUAUUCAUCUGAUGCUGUAAAUUGCCCUUCUUUCUGAGACACAGAUUAUAAGAUGCCAGAUCAUAAGACAUCAUGAUUUUAUUGUAAUUGAAUUCUUCCUAAAAAUUGAGAGGUUUCCUUUUAUUAACUUUUAAAAUAAAGAAAUAAGUAGUUUCAUUACGAUUAUUUUGCAAACUAUUGCCAGUCAGAAAUGCACUUUUUUUUUCCCUGAAGUUUUAGGAGCCGUCACUAAAACAUUAGUCUUGUGAUUGUUAAAACUUGUUUGUAAUGGGUUGGUGCAAAAGUAAUUGUGGUUUUUCCAUUACUUUCAAUGGCAAAAACCGCAAUUACUUUUGCACCAGCCUAACAAUAGUUGAUUAGUUAGACCUUUUCUGGGUUUUGUAUUGAUUAUCUUGGUGUGCAUUUAAUUAUUUUUCUGAAUUCUUCAUGGAUAAUGACAUAGUAAUUGUGAUUCUUUUAAUACCAGUUAAGCAGUAUUUGGCAACUUAAACUUCCUGGGAGCCUAACUUUACUAUGUUAAGUGAGUCAGGUGUGCUUUUUAUUUCCCUUGUUUCUCAUUUUGCCCUGUCAGUGGAUGGUAGAUGCUUUGUAUAUCUUAAAUCCCUUAAAGGAUCUUAAAGACAUCCCUCAGGUGUUCUAUUUAACUUUUAUUUUAUUUUAUUUUAUUUAUUUAUUUAUUUUGAGACUGAGUCUUGCUCUGUCGCCCAGGCUGGAGUGCAGUGGCAUGAUCUCGGCUCACUGCAACUUCUGCCUCCCAGGUUCAAGCCAUUCUCCUGCCUCGGCCUCCUGAGUAGCUGGGAUUACAGUUGCCGCCACACCCGGCUUAUUUUUUUGUAUUUUUAGUAGAGGCAGAGUUUCACCAUGUUGGCCAGGCUAGUCUCGAACUCCUGACCUCAGAUGAUCCGCCCACAUUGGCCUCCCAAAGUGCUGGGAUUACAGGUGUGAUCCACCGCACCUGGCCCUAACUUUUAAUAUACAACACACACACACACACACACACACACACACACACACACACACACACACACACACACACUAUUUCAGAAGACAGUGUGUUGCCUUACCCAGAAUGAGUGCUAGGAUUACAGGCGUGAGACAGACACACAUACACACACAUACACACACACAGAGUCUUUAUUGCAGAAGACAGUGUGUUGCCUUAUAGGCGUGAGACACACACACACACACACACACACACACACACACACACAGUCUUUAUUGCAGAAGACAGUGUGUUGCCUUACCAGAAUGAGUGCUUGGAUUACAGGCGUGAGCCACUGUGCCCAGCCCUAACUUUUAAUGUACAUCACACACACACUCACACUCACAUACACACACACACACACACUCUGACUGUCUUUAUUGCAGAAGACAGUGUGUUGCCUUACCCAGAAUGAGAUUGAAUUGUUUUGCUUCGUUUUGUUUUGUUAUUCAGUGUUGCGGUAGCAGAUGCAUUAUCAAAGGAAAAAUAUUUGGCUCCUUUAAUUCCUCUGAAAACAUGAGUAUUUUGAGUUCUGCAGCACAAUGACUGUAGGACUAAGCUAAGUCUGCUUUGCAGAUAUCUGAUCAGAUAGUCCCUUCAUUCUGUAGACGUGUAUUGGUUGGUCCAAGACACAGUGAGUAGGAGCUCUGUGGACCAAGACAAAGCUGGACUAGAGAGUACAGUUCAAACUUGGCAGUUUCUCUAACGACUCUGUAUAGCUUCUGGCUUCUACUACUGAAACAAGAGUUUAGAUCACUGAUGGAGAGGCAUAGUAAUCUGUUUGUGCUUUGGAAAAAUAUAUAAAAGUUUUUUUCCCCUAUUUUUUGCACUUUAAAUCUGUUUUGAAAUUAGAACUGAUAUACAUUUAUUUGAAUAAUGUGUAACUAUUAUGGAUCUAUUUUAAUGAACAAUUUUUACCAUUUCCCAAGCUGCCUGUUUAUUAUAAGCAUGACAUGUUUACUAUAAACCUUUUGCCCCCAUAAUUUCUUUUUUUAAAGGAAAUUAAUAUUAGUAAAAUAAACACCUCUUUAAUGGAAGCUGCAACCUUCUAGUGAUCCAAGUAGACAAUAGAUGGUGGCAUCACAGACUUUAUCUACACACUUUCGGGUCUGACCACUACCUCCCACAAUACCUAGCCAUUUUGGAAGGGGAAAACAUGCGGUGGUCUAGCUGUAUAGCUCAGGGCUUAAUUUCAGCUUCUGAGAUUGUGAUGUCAUAUUUCACUCUCAAAACAUAGGCUGAAAGCACGAAUUACUCAAAAAGUAAGCAAACCAAUACCUGGUGAAUCUAUGGACAGUCAUACACAUACAUCAGGGGAAAAUGUGUGUGUACAACCCAAAUUUACAGUAUGAUUGUCAUUCUUUGACUUUGUUUUGUAUAGCCUGACUCUGUUGAACAUGAAAUUAUUAGUACUCUAGGUUUUGGACAGCUUGAGUUCAUUUGAAUUCCUUCCUUAGGAAUAAGUUUUUAUAUACACUGCUAAAUGUGUGAUGAGAAUCAUAAAACACUAACCAGCUGAGGUAGCUGUGAUUCACUUUCCCCCCACCCUAACUUGAGAUAAAAUGAAGGACUAGGCAAGUAUUUCAUGUUGUGUGAGUGGACUUCGGUUCCUUCAGUAUUGUCUAGGUUAUUGAGUCUUUCUUUGCCUAAUAGUGGAUUCCCACUCUUAAGAUAACUUUUAUUAGUGAUAAAUCAGUUUAGGGUAUAUUCUGUAUGACAGGCAUAAAAUGUUAAGGGUGAAUGCUGGCCUUUUCCAAGAAAAGGCCACCUUAACUUGUAUGAGGAAAAAAUCCUAACUAUUCUCUUUUUUGUAUCUUUUUUUCCGUAACUGUUUUGAUUGUAUAUUUUAAAGAAACCACUUAAUUUGUGAUGCACGUAAUAUUUGUGUGAACCUGAGAAUAUGUCACAAUAGGAAAAAGCAGAAAUUAUACUUAGGGGACAUGUUAGGGGGGUAAAAAUAUUUAAGCCUCGAAUGUUUUACUGUCAUCUCCACUAACUAUUUUUACAGAAAAAGCUAAAAACUCUGUUGUAAUUAUUGUAAGUUUACUUAUUUAUACUUUUAAAUUAGGCUUUUCAUACUUAAAUUUUUUUGACAUUUGCUUUUAAUAUUUGUUUCUUAAUGUGGAAAUUGUGUAUUUUAAUAAUCAAAUUAUUAGGAUAAUAGAUAUAUUUUUAAACAUUCACCUCAUUAACAAAUAGAUCUUUGAAUUUUUAUUAGGUUUUUUGGCUCCAGACAACUGUUUAGCUUUAAUGAUAUUUCUAAAUUCCCAGUGACUUAUUAAUAAAAACAGGAAAAAUAUUUAGGUAAUGUCAUAAAAUUUAUUUUACCUUUCUCAUUUUCUGAGAAAAUAAAUGAAAAAAACCCUAGAUAUUGCUUUAUUACCAACAGUGUGUAGGUUUUUGUACAUAUGGAAAUUUGACACAAAAAAAUAGGGAAUUUGUAUAGAGAAGUUUCCCUCUUAUAAAAGGACUCCCAUUUGAUUGUUCGAAACUAUAAAAUGCACUUUUACUUUACCAUAUCUGAAAUGACAAAAUAUCGCCCUUUGGAAAACCUGACUCUUUGCACGUGUAAUUCCCAGAGUCUACCUCAGUUAACCAGGCUUAGUUUUAGGCAGGAAUGAAUUGAAUUAAAUUCAGUUCAUCAUCUAUGCAGAUUUGUUUCUUUUAAGCACAUCCUUCCCUCCUGCUGUUGCCCUCCUCCCAUUAACUUUUCUUUUUAAUCUUGAAAUUGUUUAAAAUAUUCCAUCUUUCUUUCUCUAGCAAAGUGUUUGUAUUCCAAAUAAGGCCUCUGUGAAAUGUCUGAAUUACUUUUCCCGUCUUUGUUAUGGUCAGCUUCAUUAUUUGGAUGUAUUGCAUUCAAAGCAGCAGUUCCAAACAUAACACACAUCUAUUUUCUUAGAGUUUUGUAAAUACAAACUAACCUGAUGACAUUAAAAAUUGUGGAUCCUACAUGUUCCUAUGUUCAUUCUCUAAAAACCUGAGUAACUUUAUGAAAACACACAAACCUGGAAAAACAUCACAUUUUUGUCACAUUUUUACUGACAAAUGUAUAUUCAUAUGAUGGUACGGCAGCAGGGAGUGGCCCCCAGUUAACAUGGCUGUGAGUGGACACAGUGUCUCGCAGGAUCACUGCAUGUUAUGAUGGCUUGUAAGUGCGUUGUUAAGACUUUUGUUUCAGUGUUUGUCUCCCAGUAUUUGAACCUAAUUUAAAGAAAAAGACGUUUCCAAGUUGUAUUUAUUAAAUGUGUUUUUCCUUACCUUUUGUGCUGCUACUUUGCUAAUCUCAUUAGCUUAGCUGUGUUUGUGCAUAGGUUAUAUUUGGUAAUAAAUUUAUAGAGUGUUGGUUGUCA